CCCUCCCCUGCUCUCGCAAGGAGAAAGCGGGCGACGAGCGCUCGCAGCCCGUGGGGCUGAUCCCACCUCCCGCAGGGCUCCGGUCGUGUCGCUGUCGGACCGCAGAACGCCGGGACGCAUUUCCGAGCUCGGGCCCGACCCAACCCGCUGCCAUUCUAGCUACCUAGUGGAGCCGCGGAGAGACUCUUGAACCGUGAGGCUCCUUGAUGAGAAGGUGGAGAGGCUGCCGGGCUAUUCUCCGAGCAUCUUCCGGCCGAGCUCUGCUCCUCUCCGUGCGCUUGCGGCUUCUCCUUGGGCUAGCGCGUCCGCAGUCCCUCCAAGUCCAGGCCGCAGUCACCCAGGUGGGGAGCUAGCCUGAAAGAGACAGCGGAAGGAGUUUCCUGGACUGCGCUGUCGCUCACCGACCCGCACCAAUCACCAUGCAGCUUGCCCUCGGACCCGCCCCUUUUAGGGCGUGUCCCCAGUGAGUGAUAGACGGAGCCGCCCUGCCCUGCUCAGCCCAGCCCACGUUGCUGCUUAGAUUGAAAUGCAGAACUCAAGCCUCUUUCAUCGGGGCACAGACUUCCUUUUACUUCUUCCUUUUGCCCUCUCGCCUCCUCCUCCUGGGAAGAAGCGGAGGCGCCGGCGGUCGGCCGGGAUAGCAACAGGCCGGGCCACUGAGGCGGUGCGGAAAGUUUCUGUCUGGGAGUGCGGAACUGGGGCCGGGUUGGUGUACUGCUCGGAGCAAUGGAGCCAGCCUUCGGGGAGGUGAACCAGCUGGGAGGAGUGUUCGUGAACGGGAGGCCGCUGCCCAACGCCAUCCGGCUUCGCAUCGUGGAACUGGCCCAACUGGGCAUCCGACCGUGUGACAUCAGCCGCCAGCUACGGGUCUCGCACGGCUGCGUCAGCAAGAUCCUGGCGCGAUACAACGAGACGGGCUCGAUCUUGCCAGGAGCCAUCGGGGGCAGCAAGCCCCGGGUCACUACCCCCACCGUGGUGAAACACAUCCGGACCUACAAGCAGAGAGACCCCGGCAUCUUCGCCUGGGAGAUCCGGGACCGCCUGCUGGCGGACGGCGUGUGCGACAAGUACAAUGUGCCCUCCGUGAGCUCCAUCAGCCGCAUUCUGCGCAACAAGAUCGGCAACUUGGCCCAGCAGGGUCAUUACGACUCAUACAAGCAGCACCAGCCGACGCCGCAGCCAGCGCUGCCCUACAACCACAUCUACUCGUACCCCAGCCCUAUCACGGCGGCGGCCGCCAAGGUGCCCACGCCACCCGGGGUGCCUGCCAUCCCCGGUUCGGUGGCCAUGCCGCGCACCUGGCCCUCCUCGCACUCCGUCACCGACAUCCUGGGCAUCCGCUCCAUCACCGACCAAGUGAGCGACAGCUCCCCCUACCACAGCCCCAAGGUGGAGGAGUGGAGCAGCCUGGGCCGCAACAACUUCCCCGCCGCCGCCCCGCACGCGGUGAACGGGUUGGAGAAGGGAGCCCUGGAGCAGGAAGCCAAGUACGGUCAGGCACCAAAUGGUCUCCCAGCUGUGGGCAGUUUUGUGUCAGCAUCCAGCAUGGCUCCUUACCCUACCCCAGCCCAAGUGUCGCCUUACAUGACCUACAGUGCUGCUCCUUCUGGUUAUGUUGCUGGACAUGGGUGGCAACAUGCUGGGGGCACCUCAUUGUCUCCCCACAACUGUGACAUUCCGGCAUCGCUGGCGUUCAAGGGAAUGCAGGCAGCCAGAGAAGGUAGUCAUUCUGUCACGGCUUCCGCGCUCUGAUGGGAAAUUCCGUCUCCAGCAGCUUCACCCGGGUCUCCCUGUCUCAGCACCUCCUCCCCCAAUUCCCAGGUCUCACAUCCCACCCCUCCUGCCCUCCAACCCUUCUGCCUUGAAAGCUGGCUGUACGGACUCACAUCCUUUGUGCUAAUGACACUUACAUAUUUCUUGCCAUAACUUUUCUCUUGCAGAAAAACUGACAUGACUUUAGGAUUUAAAAACAAGAGCAACAAUAAGCAUUGAAUGAGACAUUUGUGUUGCCCACAUACUGUCUUAACAUAACAAAGAAACCUACACCCCUCAAAGGGUUUAAGGAACUUUACAAACUAGUCUUUGGUAAAACCACAUGUGUAUAUUUAUUCUAAAUCAACCUGAACUUUUGAAAUGUGCAAUUGUUGAGAUUUUGCAAAAUCAAUAAAGGAAAAUACUUAUAGAAAAAAUUAUGCUACACCCUCUAAUCAAAUAUGGUAACCAAGUAAGCUUUAAUUCAUCAUUAGGAAACAAAUCAAUAAGUGACUUGUUUGAGUGAUCCUUUGUUUAAGACAUGACCUAUUUUGUUGAAAAAUAUAUGUAGAACCCAAGCAAUAUCUGAAUCUAGCUCUCCCUGGUGUUUUGACUUGGUUCCAAAUACAAUAAUGUUUAUAUUUUCUAUUAGUUUGUAAAUACGGACUCUGGAUGGUGCAUUUGUGUCUUCAUUCCAUAAGAUAUUCCCCUCCCCUCAGCCCCACCCCCUCUCUAUUUUUUUCUUUCUUUUUUGCAAAGGUGACUUUCUGGCAACGUCUUUGUCUCUGUUUGGUGGUGGGCUGCUCGGGCUCCUGGACCUGGACUUGCCCCCAAAUUUUGUGUAUGCAGUGAAGGCUUCAACAUCUCAUGAAGGACACUUUAUUUCUACAGCAGAGGACACGAAAAACAGAUAAAACAAGCCAGUCUCCCAUUUUGUACCUAAUCAAACAACACACAUGCUAAGCAUAUAAAGACAAGAGGGUGGAAAAUAUCUGAACAAGAAGGCUCUAAAGGAAGUCACUUAGAAACUUAAGUUUAAUGUGAAAUGUUUUGCAAAGAUGCUUAAAAUGAACUUUGUGUUAAGAAAACCACUGUGAAACUAAAUUGUCCUAUUAUUGUUGGCUUACCUGUGUGUUCAGCAAUCUCAGCCCCAAAUAAUGUUGUAAUUUAAAGAAAAUGGAAAAUUCUGCUCUAAUGAAUGUAACAAUGGCUUGCUGUGAAGUUUACAUUGUUGUACAGAAGCAUGUUUCGCAUGUAGGUAAACUGGUGGUGGUACUAGAAAUACAAUGUUAUUUAAUUUUAACAAAUUCCCUUUAUUCAUUUCUGAAAUUACAGGACACAGUUUAACUCAUAAACCUUUCUAGACCAAUUUAUUUUUCACUUUAAUGUUAAUAACAGUUGUGGAGUAUAUGUGUGUGUGAGCAUGUGAGUAUGUGUUGUAUUUUAAAACAAUUGAUUUUCUGGGGCAAAAUUCUACAGUUUUUAAUCCCUUCUGUUUAGGAAGUUCUUCCUGUUUGGCAAUAUAGGCUUAAAAAUAUGUUUUUAGGACAUUGGUACAAUUCAGCUGUUGGAAAAUUAAUAUAUUGAGGGUUUUUUGGUACUAAUUCUGUGCAAUAACUAAAAGAGCACCUCACUGGAUAUGGAUGUUGAAGAUGGAUUCCCUAGGUGAUUUUAAUUUCUUCCGGUCUGUGCUGUGCACAGUCUACAUGGCAAUGCGGUUCCACCACAUCGGUUUCGUGGCUUCGUUUAAAACUCAGAUGGCUAGAUUAGUUAGGUUUUCAAAUCACUAGGAUGUAAACAGUAAGCAGAUUUCUGACACACAAAUUAUGUUAGAGUGACUGCUUUUUUCAGACAGCAGAUAUCUUAUAGAGAGCUUUGAACUGCAUUUAUUUCUAAAGCAACCGAAAUUCAGUGCUACAAAUAGAGGAUUAUAACUUCAGGAGAAGAAUAAGCAGAAGGAGCAGAUGAACUCUCAGGGCCAUAGUCUUCCUUUGAUCUUGUAAAACUUCCAUUGACAUCUGGAGUUCCCAGUCUGGUGAGAAAAUAGACUAUAAACUGAAUGGAACAAAGAUCCAAUCCAAUAUUUUGGUGGAGACUUCUUUAAAACCAUACCAUACAGGGACUCUCCUGUCAUCUGAAAAACUGAUGUAAGGUACAGAACUAUUCUUUAUCAAAUGUUUUUAGGUGGCUGUUAGGGGGCUUUAAAAAAUAUUACUUGCUUGUGUGGAAAUGCAAAUAAUGUUAUUUUCUUUAUCUAAAUUAAGAAAUCUCUUGUUAUUGUGCUAUUUAUAAUUUUUUUCUGGUUCUUGUAUUUUAAAAAAUCUAAUAUUAAUGGUAUUGAAGUUUCCUUUUCUCCCUCUAGGUCUUAACAGUGAAUUCACAUGGAGUAAUUUUUAAAAGAUAUCAGAUACAAUUUGCUAUUCAAAGAAAAUUAUGAUUUAAAGCCACUUUUUAAAAUACGAGAAGGAAAAUAGGAUGGAUUAAAGGGUUAACUUUUAAAGAUUAUUAUUGGUUAAUGUUGACAUAUUUCCUCUAUCUCAUAGAUGGUAAAAGUGUUGCUUUUAAACUGGCAAAUGCACUCUUCAGAAAUCCUUUUCUAUCUGAUCCACAUGGAGAGGUUAAAGGUUCAAUUUCAUGACCUCUAUGCAGGCAGCGCUCUCAUUGGAUGUAAGAAUAUUACCUGCAAGGAUAGAAUGCAGUUGUGCAACAGAGACACAUUCUUAUUUCUUUUUUUUCACAAUUUUGUUUUGUUUUUAAUGACCCUUUUAUUGAAUAUUGGACUGAAAUAUAAAUUUUAAAAAACACGUUGGAAAGGAUGUACAACAGAAGGCUAUGUAUGUAUAUACAGUAUGUCAAAAGCCUUUUAUUUUUAUACUUCAAAUGCUCUAAAUUAAUAAAAAGUAAUAAUUA